AGCUUGAAAUGAAUUUUAAAGGAUGACUGAUGGUCCCUGGAAGAGAAACAGUAAACAAAUAAGGUUUCAGGCACAGAACUGUAUAUCCAAUAAUAGUGAAAUGGAUCCCACUAAUUAUGACAGAAAUGAUGAUACAUUUAAAUGACUUGGAUGUUUUAUAGGUUGGCACUCAUCAUGAGCCCCUGUUCUCAUUCUGCAAAUGGUGAAGCUCUCUAUUGUCCUGACCCCACAGUUCCUGUCCCAUGACCAGGGCCAGCUCACCAAGGAGCUGCAGCAGCAUGUAAAGUCAGUGACAUGCCCAUGCGAGUACCUGAGGAAGGUUAUCAAUACUCUGGCUGACCAUCAUCAUCGUGGGACUGACUUUGGUGGAAGUCCUUGGUUACAUGUCAUUAUUGCGUUUCCGACAAGUUAUAAAGUUGUCAUUACCCUCUGGAUAGUUUACCUUUGGGUGUCUCUCCUGAAGACUAUCUUCUGGUCUCGAAAUGGACAUGAUGGAUCCACGGAUGUACAGCAGAGAGCCUGGAGGUCCAACCGCCGUAGACAGGAAGGGCUGAGGUCCAUUUGUAUGCACACAAAGAAAAGAGUUUCUUCCUUUCGAGGAAAUAAAAUUGGCCUGAAAGACGUCAUUACUCUACGGAGACAUGUGGAAACAAAAGUUAGAGCUAAAAUCCGUAAGAGGAAGGUGACAACGAAAAUCAACCAUCAUGACAAAAUCAAUGGAAAGAGGAAGACCGCCAGAAAACAGAAAAUGUUUCAACGUGCGCAAGAGUUGCGGCGGCGAGCAGAGGACUACCACAAAUGCAAAAUCCCCCCUUCUGCAAGAAAGGCUCUUUGCAACUGGGUCAGAAUGGCGGCAGCGGAGCAUCGUCAUUCUUCAGGAUUGCCCUACUGGCCCUACCUCACAGCUGAAACUUUAAAAAACAGGAUGGGCCACCAGCCACCUCCUCCAACUCAACAACAUUCUAUAACUGAUAACUCCCUGAGCCUCAAGACACCUCCCGAGUGUCUGCUCACUCCCCUUCCACCCUCAGCGGAUGAUAAUCUCAAGACACCUUCCGAGCGUCAGCUCACUGCCCUUCCACCCUCAGCAGAUGAUAAUAUCAAUACACCUGCCGAGCGUCUGCGGGGGCCGCUUCCACCCUCAGCGGAUGAUAAUCUCAAGACACCUUCCGAGCGUCAGCUCACUCCCCUUCCACCCUCAGCUCCACCCUCAGCAGAUGAUAAUAUCAAGACACCUGCCGAGCGUCUGCGGGGGCCGCUUCCACCCUCAGCGGAUGAUAAUCUCAAGACACCUUCCGAGCGUCAGCUCACUCCCCUUCCACCCUCAGCUCCACCCUCAGCAGAUGAUAAUAUCAAGACACGCCUUCCACCCUCAGCGGAUGAUCUCAAGACACCUUCCGAGCGUCAGCUCACUCCCCUUCCACCCUCAGCUCCACCCUCAGCAGAUGAUAAUAUCAAGAUACCUGCUGAGCGUCUGCGGAUUCCGCUUCCACCAUCAGCCGAUGAUAAUCUCAAGACACCUUCCGAGCGUCAGCUCACUCCCCUUCCACCCUCAGCUCCACCCUCAGCAGAUGAUAAUAUCAAGACACCUGCCGAGCGUCUGCGGGGGCCGCUUCCACCCUCAGCGGAUGAUAAUCUCAAGACACCUUCCGAGCGUCAGCUCACUCCCCUUCCACCCUCAGCUCCACCCUCAGCAGAUGAUAAUAUCAAGACACCUGCCUUCCACCCUCAGCGGAUGAUCUCAAGACACCUUCCGAGCGUCAGCUCACUCCCCUUCCACCCUCAGCUCCACCCUCAGCAGAUGAUAAUAUCAAGAUACCUGCUGAGCGUCUGCGGAUUCCGCUUCCACCAUCAGCCGAUGAUAAUCUCAAGACACCUUCCGAGCGUCAGCUCACUCCCCUUCCACCCUCAGCUCCACCCUCAGCAGAUGAUAAUAUCAAGACACCUGCCGAGCGUCUGCGGGGGCCGCUUCCACCCUCAGCGGAUGAUAAUCUCAAGACACCUUCCGAGCGUCAGCUCACUCCCCUUCCACCCUCAGCUCCACCCUCAGCAGAUGAUAAUAUCAAGACACCUGCCGAGCGUCUGCGGGGGCCGCUUCCACCCUCAGCAGAUGAUAAUCUCAAGACACCUUCCGAGCGUCAGCUCACUCCCCUUCCACCCUCAGCUCCACCCUCAGCAGAUGAUAAUAUCAAGACACCUGCCGAGCGUCUGCGGGCCGCUUCCACCCUCAGCGGAUGAUAAUCUCAAGACACCUUCCGAGCGUCAGCUCACUCCCUUUCCACCCUCAGCUCCACCCUCAGCAGAUGAUAAUAUCAAGACACCUGCCGAGCGUCUGCGGGGGCGUCUGCGGGGGCCGCUUCCACCCUCAGCGGAUGAUAAUCUCAAGACACCUUCCGAGCGUCAGCUCACUCCCCUUCCACCCUCAGCUCCACCCUCAGCAGAUGAUAAUAUCAAGACACCUGCCGAGCGUCUGCGGGGGCCGCUUCCACCCUCAGCGGAUGAUAAUCUCAAGACACCUUCCGAGCGUCAGCUCACUCCCUUUCCACCCUCAGCUCCACCCUCAGCAGAUGAUAAUAUCAAGACACCUGCUGAGCGUCUGCGGGGGCCGCUUCCACCCUCAGCGGAUGAUAAUCUCAAGACACCUUCCGAGCGUCAGCUCACUCCCCUUCCACCCUCAGCUCCACCCUCAGCAGAUGAUAAUAUCAAGACACCUGCCGAGCGUCUGCGGGGGCCGCUUCCACCCUCAGCCGAUGAUAAUCUCAAGACACCUCCCUUAGCUACUCAGGAGGCUGAGGCAGAAAAACCACGCAAACCCAAGAGGCAGAGGGCGGCUGAGAUGGAACCACCUCCCGAACCCAAGAGGCGGAGGGUCGGUGACGUGGAACCGUCACGCAAACCCAAGAGGCGGAGGGCCGCUGACGUGGAACCAUCAUCACCCGAACCCAAGAGGCGGAGGGUCGGUGAUGUGGAACCGUCACGCAAACCCAAGAGGCGGAGGGCCGCUGACGUGGAACCAUCAUCACCCGAACCCAAGAGGCGGAGGGUCGGUGACGUGGAACCGUCACGCAAACCCAAGAGGCGGAGGGCCGCUGACGUGGAACCAUCAUUACCCGAACCCAAGAGGCGGAGGUUGAGCUGAGAAGAGGCCAGUGCACUCAAGCCUGAGCAAUAAGAAUAAAACCGAGUAGAACAAAAUAAAAAAUUCAAAAAACAAAACAAAACCCACACUCCAAAAACUAACAAAGAAUAAAUAAAUAAUAUAAAAAUAAAAUAAA